AACCCCAGGACAGCGGACAGCGGGCCGGGCACUUCCAAAGGCGCAGGAGCGAAGCAGCCCUCUCCAGCCGUGCACUGCACCUCCGCGGCCCGCGGGCGAGAUUGGGGUCCCGGUGGGAAGCAGACGCGCAAUCGGGGAGAAGCUCCAGCAGUGGAGGAAGAGUCCAGGGAGUUUCAGCUGGGCAGAAGGGGCGCAGAGGCUUGGGGCCAAGCGGAGUUUGCCCUGCGGGUCCUGCGCAAGGCCCCAGUGCCCCGGCUAAACCUUUGCCGCAGGAUCCCGGAGCCGGCGUCCUUCAAGGAGCACAGAGGGCCCCGUAGCACGCCCCUUGCCCAGCGCCACCGACCCUUAAGCAGCGUCAAGGAAGGAGUCCCGAUCAAGGACAGGGAUCUGCGGCCAUGGCCGAGGCCGCGGAGCCGGAGGGGGUUGCCCCGGGUCCCCAGGGGCCGCCGGAGGUCCCCGCGCCUCUGGCUGAGAGACCCGGAGAGCCAGGAGCCGCGGGCGGGGAGGCAGAAGGGCCGGAGGGGAGCGAGGGCGCAGAGGAGGCGCCGAGGGGCGCCGCCGCUGUGAAGGAGGCAGGAGGCGGCGGGCCAGACAGGGGCCCGGAGGCCGAGGCGCGGGGCACGAGGGGGGCGCACGGCGAGACUGAGGCCGAGGAGGGAGCCCCGGAGGGUGCCGAGGUGCCCCAAGGAGGGGAGGAGACAAGCGGCGCGCAGCAGGUGGAGGGGGCGAGCCCGGGACGCGGCGCGCAGGGCGAGCCCCGCGGGGAGGCUCAGAGGGAGCCCGAGGACUCUGCGGCCCCCGAGAGGCAGGAGGAGGCGGAGCAGAGGCCUGAGGUCCCGGAAGGUAGCGCGUCCGGGGAGGCGGGGGACAGCGUAGACGCGGAGGGCCCGCUGGGGGACAACAUAGAAGCGGAGGGCCCGGCGGGCGACAGCGUAGAGGCGGAGGGCCGGGUGGGGGACAGCGUAGACGCGGAAGGUCCGGCGGGGGACAGCGUAGACGCGGAGGGCCCGCUGGGGGACAACAUACAAGCCGAGGGCCCGGCGGGGGACAGCGUAGACGCGGAGGGCCGGGUGGGGGACAGCGUAGACGCGGAAGGUCCGGCGGGGGACAGCGUAGACGCGGAGGGCCGGGUGGGGGACAGCGUAGAGGCGGGGGACCCGGCGGGGGACGGCGUAGAAGCGGGGGUCCCGGCGGGGGACAGCGUAGAAGCCGAAGGCCCGGCGGGGGACAGCAUGGACGCCGAGGGUCCGGCAGGAAGGGCGCGCCGGGUCUCGGGUGAGCCGCAGCAAUCGGGGGACGGCAGCCUCUCGCCCCAGGCCGAGGCAAUUGAGGUCGCAGCCGGGGAGAGUGCGGGGCGCAGCCCCGGUGAGCUCGCCUGGGACGCAGCGGAGGAGGCGGAGGUCCCGGGGGUAAAGGGGUCCGAAGAAGCGGCCCCCGGGGACGCAAGGGCAGACGCUGGCGAGGACAGGGUAGGGGAUGGGCCACAGCAGGAGCCGGGGGAGGACGAAGAGAGACGAGAGCGGAGCCCGGAGGGGCCAAGGGAGGAGGAAGCAGCGGGGGGCGAAGAGGAAUCCCCCGACAGCAGCCCACAUGGGGAGGCCUCCAGGGGCGCCGCGGAGCCUGAGGCCCAGCUCAGCAACCACCUGGCCGAGGAGGGCCCCGCCGAGGGUAGCGGCGAGGCCGCGCGCGUGAACGGCCGCCGGGAGGACGGAGAGGCGUCCGAGCCCCGGGCCCUGGGGCAGGAGCACGACAUCACCCUCUUCGUCAAGGUAAAACUUACUGCAUUAGGCUGUUCUCGCAUUGCUAUAAAGAAAUACCUGAGAGCUGGUUAUGAUGGUGAGAGUAUCGGAAAUUGCCCGUUUUCUCAGCGUCUCUUUAUGAUUCUCUGGCUGAAAGGCGUUAUAUUUAAUGUGACCACAGUGGACCUGAAAAGGAAACCCGCAGACCUGCAGAACCUGGCUCCCGGAACAAACCCUCCUUUCAUGACUUUUGAUGGUGAAGUCAAGACGGAUGUGAAUAAGAUCGAGGAGUUCUUAGAGGAGAAAUUAGCUCCCCCGAGGUAUCCCAAGCUGGGGACCCAACAUCCCGAAUCUAAUUCCGCAGGAAAUGACGUGUUUGCCAAAUUCUCAGCGUUUAUAAAAAACACGAAGAAGGAUGCAAAUGAGAUUCAUGAAAAGAACCUGCUGAAGGCCCUGAGGAAGCUGGAUAAUUACUUAAAUAGCCCUCUGCCUGAUGAAAUAGAUGCCUACAGCACCGAGGAUGUCACUGUUUCUGGAAGGAAGUUUCUGGAUGGGGACGAGCUGACGCUGGCUGACUGCAACCUCUUACCCAAGCUCCAUAUUAUUAAGAUUGUGGCCAAGAAGUACAGAGAUUUUGAAUUUCCUUCUGAAAUGACUGGCAUCUGGAGAUACUUGAAUAAUGCUUAUGCUAGAGAUGAGUUCACAAAUACGUGUCCAGCUGAUCAAGAGAUUGAACACGCAUAUUCAGAUGUUGCAAAAAGAAUGAAAUGAAGCUGGGCUGUUUUCUGUCUUAUUUCUCAGUUGAGUGAGCAAGGAUACGAAAACAGUGUGUUUGAAAACAAAUUAGGUUUGGGUUCAAUUCCUUCAAUUUUUAAAAAACUGGUCUCUGAGAGUUUUUUAAAUCAUUGAGAGCCUGUUUUUCUUCUCUAAAACAUUAGUUUAAUUUUCUUCAAAAUGAAAAUACUGCUUUGUAAUUACAAAAUGAGACACACCUAUCUUGAUAUUUUAAAGCAAUAUCAGAGGGUGUAAAGAAGGACAUUUUAACAAUCGCCUUCAAUUUUACUCCACUUAAUUACCGAAAACUUACUGGAGAACAUGUUCCAAAUCUUCAGUAUCUUGUUCUCUCUCUCUCUCUCUCUCUCUCUCUCUAUCACACACACACACACACACACACACACACACACACACAAUUUCAUUCAUAUAUGGUAUUGCAUUAUUUUAUUUUAAAGCACUGGUGAGGGGACCUCUUGGUGAUUCCUGGAUGAUCAUACACAGAGGACUUACACCAUACAAAAAUAUUGGGCACCGCAGUGCCAGAGAAGAUGCUUGAGGUUAGAUUUUAAGGAGUGGGGAAUUGUGAAGCCCACAGAUGCGCACGCAAUGACCAGCAGGAACCGGAAGCCCUGGGUCACCCCCACUCUGCCUCAUUUCUGCCUCCAGGAUGCCACUGCCUCUGCUUCCAGGAAAGGCAAGGGGGAGGGUGCUUAUCCGUGUCUCUGGUUCCAGCUUCCUGUCUUUGCUCCCUCCCCUCUCUUAGAGACUGUGCCUUCAGCAGGACUCUUAAUAUCUGCUGCAACUUGGAGAACCUCCCUGCCCUGAAAUGUGAACCAAGCACACUUUGGUUCCUUCUCCGGGCGGCUCUCUCUGAGACCCAAGGCUGCAGUCCCUCAGUGCUGGUGGUAUCGUGUGGGGAUAGCAAUACUUCUCUGCCCUUCAUUGUCUCAUCUAGACAUCAAGCAGGGAAAAUCCAGGGAGAUUAAAUUCAUGGUGACAAGUCCUGGGCAGUUCUGGUAAACGGUCCAGUUAGGGAGGGAGUAGAAACUAUUGACUCAAAAGAGUUUCUGGCUGAUCUGUGGCUUUGCCUCCACCAUCCCUAACCAACCUCUCAUCACAGCUUUGUGUGUGGGCUGAGUGCUGGCCUUAACCCUAGGCGUGGAAGAGAAAAUGUGAGGUUGUUUAGAUACUCAUCAGGACCUCACAGGAGCUGAGACUUAUCAGCCAGAAUGUGUUCUUCGGACAGUCGUACACAUCUUACAGAAAACCCUCCUUGUAGAGUUGGUUGUGGUAUGUGUUUGAUGCUAUAAAGCUCAUUUUUAAUGUGUACACCUGCUCUAGGGACGAUUCGUUUGAAAGAGAGUAAGAUGCAUUAACAGAAACUAUCCUGGGAUUAGGUGAAAAAUGUCUAGCAAAAGAAACAAAGUCUUUAAUAGAGUGGCCUCUUUCGCUCUUCGAUUAUGACUGCUGCAGUUUUACCCCAGCAGUCAGCUGUCUUUGUCAACCAUACGUUUUUGGAGAUUGGGUCUAGCACAUGUCACCCUUGUCCACGUUGUUUCACAUCUGGUUAGGGGGCAGAUUUUAAAAUGUAGUUUUGUAAUGUUACAUUUAAGCAUGAUAAAUGAUUAGACUACCAGAUGUUACUAGUGCUAACUUUGUAUUCUUAGACAUUAAAAUGAUUGACAUAAACUCUUUGUGCCUUGAAAAUGAAACAAAUUAUAAAAAUGUUUAAAUGGAA